CUGUACAGCAGCCUGGGCCAUGUCGGCGCCGCCGGCCCUGCAGAUCCGGGAGGCAAACGCACACCUGGCAGCCGUGCACCGGCGCGCAGCGGAGCUGGAGGCGCGGCUGGACGCGGCGGAGCGCACGGUGCACGCCCAAGCCGAGCGCCUGGCCCUCCACGACCAGCAGCUGCGCGCCGCCCUAGACGAACUGGGUCGCGCCAAGGACCGUGAGAUUGCCACACUCCAGGAGCAGCUGAUGACCUCAGAAGCCACUGUCCACAGCCUGCAGGCCACCGUGCACCAGAGGGACGAGCUCAUUAGGCAGUUGCAGCCCCGGGCUGAGCUGCUGCAGGACAUCUGCCGCCGCCGGCCACCCCUGGCUGGGCUGCUGGAUGCCCUGGCUGAGGCUGAGCGCCUGGGGCCCCUGCCGGCCAGUGACCCCGGCCACCCACCCCCCGGUGGGCCUGGUCCACCCCUUGACAACAGCACUGGGGAAGAGGCGGACAGGGACCACCUCCAGCCUGCAGUGUUUGGGACCACAGUGUGAGCCCGGAAUGCAGAUUACAGAAUGGAGACAGAAAGCCACUGCUGUCAGUGUCCUUGGGAGUCACCAGCACCCUGCAGGGGGACCCUACGGCAGAGCCAAAGUCCUGUCUAAGCAUCAGAACAGGCUGAACAGUCAAAAAGUUUUCAAAUAGGCCCACAGGCCAGGUGCAGACGUUUAACCCAGACAGAAGUGUUCUUGUUUGUUUUUAAGCUUUGAAUCAGUCACCCUUGCUAAAAACCUGGCAAUGCAAACACAAAGAUCUGGAUUUCUGGCAAGACUUGGCCAAGCUUGCCUGGAGUUCAGGGCACCCUCUUUAGCCAGGGUGUGAGUUUCUGUUUUUUGUUUUUUUUUUUUUAAGACAGAGUCCCACUCUGUCGCCCUGGCUGGGGUGCAGUGGUGCGAUUUUGGCUAACUGCAACCUCCGCCUCCCAGGUUCAAGCGAUUCUCCUGUCUCAUCCUUCAGAGUAGCUGGGAUUACAGGCGCCCACCACCACACCCGGAUAUUUUAUAUUUUUGGUAGAGACCGGGGAGGGGAGGGGGUUUCACCAUGUUGACCAGGCUGGUCUCAAACUCCUGACCUUAGGUGAUCCACCCGCCUCGGCCUUCGAAAGUGCUGCAGUUAUAGGUGUAAGCCACCGCGCCCGGCCCUAGCCUAGCUUUUGUAGCAUGCAACUGUCUCCUUUUUAUACGCCCUAAAGAAUAUAUUUUUGAACUCCUUGUUUCUGCGCUGUCCUUCUUAGCCCAGGACAUUCAGGGUGCUUUGCUUGUUGUCAAACCAGGGAAAGGAGAAAACUCCUGUGCCUUUCUGGGCCAGCCUGUCACCCUGGCCUGGUCGGCAGCCAUUCCCCUACCUCCUCACUCAGGAACUGUCACACCAGGAACCGGCGAGGGGCACAGCCUGUUUCAGACCAGAAAGGUCGGAGGCCACCCACGGCCUUCAGGAUGGCGCCCGCCUGCCUGCCUGGCAACAGUGACCCCUCAGUGCAGUAACAAUGGGCCCAUUUUCUCCUCUGGAUGAACAAGGAGGGGGGUUGUUUGUACAAAGGAAAGGCAGGCUGGGGCCUGUCUGUGCUCAAGAAUAAACCGGAUGAUUUCCUGGCCUGGGGGCAAGAGGGAGGCCCUCUGUGUUAUUUGUGCCUCCUGGUAGGGUCCUGCUGGGCCAGGUAGAAUCUAGGGAGUGUAGGCCAAGCACUCUCUACAGCGAUUGCAUCUAAUCUUCGAGUUUCCCUGUAGACACAGGCUUUGUCCUCAUUUUACAGCUGUGGAAAGUGAGGCCCAGGCCGGGCGCGGUGUCUCACGCCUGUAAUCCCAGCACUUUGGGAUGCGGGUGGAUCACCUGAGGUCAGGAGUUCGAGACCACCCUGGCCAACAUGGUGAAACCCCGUCUCUACUAAAAAUACUAAAAUUAGCCGGGCUUGGUGGCGGGUGCCUGUAAUCCCAGCUACUGAACCCGGGAGGCGGAGGUUGCAGUGAGUGGAGAUUGCACCACUGCACUCCAGCCUGGGAGACAGAGUGAGACUCAGUCUCAAAGAAAACAACAACAACAACAACAACAACAACAACAACAACAAACAGAGGCCCAGAGGUGUGAAGGGAACACACUCCGGGUCUGGAGGGCCAGGGCCACUUCCAAUUCUGGGGGAAGUUAUUGCUGAAAUUCUGUUUUCUUUCUUUCUUUCUUUUUUUUUUAAAGAGACAAAGUCUCACUGUU